CCUGGGCGACAGCGAGACUCCAUCUCAAUAAAUAAAAAAAAAAAAGAGUUGUUAUCAGUAGAAGGGAAUGUCUGGUUACAGUAUGGCGUUGUGCAGAUGAAGGUCUUAUCGCAGAUGAAGCCACCAGGUCACAAGCCUCAGAGAGAAUCAACUAUAAAUGCUUCUCAUCAGACUCAAGGCCUGAGGUGAUGCUGAUGCUGUGCCUGAAUUCCAGCAGGGAGGAGGCAUGAGGGCAGUGCUGUCACAGAAGACAACACCGCUCCCUCGUUACCUGUGGCCCGGCCACCUCAGCGGCCCAAGGAGGCUCACCUGGUCAUGGUGCAGUGACCACAGGACCCCCACAUGCCGGGAGCUGGGUUCGCCCCACCCCACCCCCUGCACCGGGCCAGCGAGGGGAUGGCCCAGAAGAGGGGGAGGACCAUGUGGAUUCACCAGUGCUGGACAUGUGCUCUGUGGCUACCCCCUCUGCCUACUCUCUGGCCCGAUACAGGGGUGUGGGACAGGCCUGGGUGACUCCAGCAUGGCUUUCCUCUCCAGGACGUCACCGGUGGCAGCUGCUUCCUUCCAGAGCCGGCAGGAGGCCAGAGGCUCCAUCCUGCUUCAGAGCUGCCAGCUGCCCCCGCAAUGGCUGAGCACCGAAGCAUGGACGGGAGAAUGGAAGCAGCCACACGGGGGGGCUCUCACCUCCAGAUCGCCUGGGCCUGUGGCUCCCCAGAGGCCCUGCCACCUGAAGGGAUGGCAGCACAGACCCACUCAGCACAACGCUGCCUGCAAACAGGGCCAGGCUGCAGCCCAGACGCCCCCCAGGCCGGGGCCACCAUCAGCACCACCACCACCACCCAAGGAGGGGCACCAGGAGGGGCUGGUGGAGCUGCCCGCCUCGUUCCGGGAGCUGCUCACCUUCUUCUGCACCAAUGCCACCAUCCACGGCGCCAUCCGCCUGGUCUGCUCCCGCGGGAACCGCCUCAAGACGACGUCCUGGGGGCUGCUGUCCCUGGGAGCCCUGGUCGCGCUCUGCUGGCAGCUGGGGCUCCUCUUUGAGCGUCACUGGCACCGCCCGGUCCUCAUGGCCGUCUCUGUGCACUCGGAGCGCAAGCUGCUCCCGCUGGUCACCCUGUGUGACGGGAACCCACGUCGGCCGAGUCCGGUCCUCCGCCAUCUGGAGCUGCUGGACGAGUUUGCCAGGGAGAACAUUGACUCCCUGUACAACGUCAACCUCAGCAAAGGCAGAGCCGCCCUCUCCGCCACUGUCCCCCGCCACGAGCCCCCCUUCCACCUGGACCGGGAGAUCCGUCUGCAGAGGCUGAGCCACUCGGGCAGCCGGGUCAGAGUGGGGUUCAGACUGUGCAACAGCACGGGCGGCGACUGCUUUUACCGAGGCUACACGUCAGGCGUGGCGGCUGUCCAGGACUGGUACCACUUCCACUAUGUGGAUAUCCUGGCCCUGCUGCCCGCGGCAUGGGAGGACAGCCACGGGAGCCAGGACGGCCACUUCGUCCUCUCCUGCAGUUACGAUGGCCUGGACUGCCAGGCCCGACAGUUCCGGACCUUCCACCACCCCACCUACGGCAGCUGCUACACGGUCGAUGGCGUCUGGACAGCUCAGCGCCCCGGCAUCACCCACGGAGUCGGCCUGGUCCUCAGGGUUGAGCAGCAGCCUCACCUCCCUCUGCUGUCCACGCUGGCCGGCAUCAGGGUCAUGGUUCACGGCCGUAACCACACGCCCUUCCUGGGGCACCACAGCUUCAGCGUCCGGCCAGGGACGGAGGCCACCAUCAGCAUCCGAGAGGACGAGGUGCACCGGCUCGGGAGCCCCUACGGCCACUGCACCGCCGGCGGGGAAGGCGUGGAGGUGGAGCUGCUACACAACACCUCCUACACCAGGCAGGCCUGCCUGGUGUCCUGCUUCCAGCAGCUGAUGGUGGAGACCUGCUCCUGUGGCUACUACCUCCACCCUCUGCCGGCGGGGGCUGAGUACUGCAGCUCUGCCCGGCACCCUGCCUGGGGACACUGCUUCUACCGCCUCUACCAGGACCUGGAGACCCACCGGCUCCCCUGUACCUCCCGCUGCCCCAGGCCCUGCAGGGAGUCUGCAUUCAAGCUCUCCACUGGGACCUCCAGGUGGCCUUCCGCCAAGUCAGCUGGAUGGACUCUGGCCACGCUAGGUGAACAGGGGCUGCCGCAUCAGAGCCACAGACAGAGGAGCAGCCUGGCCAAAAUCAACAUCGUCUACCAGGAGCUCAACUACCGCUCAGUGGAGGAGGCGCCCGUGUACUCGGUGCCGCAGCUGCUCUCGGCCAUGGGCAGCCUCUGCAGCCUGUGGUUUGGGGCCUCCGUCCUCUCCCUCCUGGAGCUCCUGGAGCUGCUGCUCGAUGCUUCUGCCCUCACCCUGGUGCUAGGCGGCCGCCGGCUCCGCAGGGCGUGGUUCUCCUGGCCCAGAGCCAGCCCUGCCUCAGGGGCGUCCAGCAUCAAGCCAGAGGCCAGUCAGAUGCCCCCGCCUGCAGGCGGCACGUCAGAUGACCCGGAGCCCAGCGGGCCUCAUCUCCCACGGGUGAUGCUUCCAGGGGUUCUGGCGGGAGUCUCAGCCGAAGAGAGCUGGGCUGGGCCCCAGCCCCUUGAGACUCUGGACACCUGAACCAGACCUGCCAGGGCUGUGCGAUCUCUUGGCCUGGUCCUUGCAGCUGUGGCAGCAGCAGGCUCCCCAGCGGCCCAGGGUGGGCCAGACCAGCAGCCCAGGAAGCAGCACACGCGGCCGUGGGGAGGCAGGCACCGGGCAUGUCGGCGCCUCUGGUCAAACCACCUACACUGCCUGGGGUGGGUCUCAAGGAGGCCCGGGGCGGAGGGGGGUUCCCGCGUGCACACGAGUGCGGCUGGACGUGCCGACACGCGGUGAUGUACCCAUGCUCCGUGUGUCUGUGUCUGCAUGUCCACACGUCUGAUGCACCUGUGUACGUGUGUCAAGCCUAGCCACCUCAGCUGCAGGGAGGCAGAAGGCAAGGCAGGCCCCACGGACACACUUGGGCUGCUCUGAAAUAAAGCUGUUGACUCCA